CUAGCGAAAAAUGAUUUGGCUCGGACUGUCCCGUGACAGGCGGUGCGAGGAGGCCAGGCCCGCGCCCGCCGAGCCCUAGGGCCGCUGCUGCCGACAGCCAUGGAGGACGAGCAGCCUGACAGCCUGGAGGGCUGGGUGCCGGUCCGGGAGGGCCUCUUCGCCGAGCCCGAGAGGCACCGGCUGCGCUUCCUGGUGGCCUGGAACGGCGCGGAGGGCAAGUUCGCUGUGACUUGUCACGACCGUACCGCGCAGCAGCGGCGGCUGCGCGAGGGGGCCCGGUUGGGGCCCGAGCCCGAGCCCAAGCCUGAGGCCGCCGUCUCCCCGUCCAGCUGGGCCGGCCUGCUCUCGGCCGCGGGGCUCCGCGGCGCGCACCGGCAGUUGGCGGCGCUGUGGCCGCCUCUGGAGCGCUGCUUCCCGCGGCUGCCGCCGGAGCUGGACGUGGGCGGCGGCGGGGCCUGGGGUCUGGGGCUCGGGCUGUGGGCGCUGCUGUGGCCGACGCGCGCGGGUCCCGGCGAGGCGGCGCUGCAGGAGCUGUGCGGGCAGCUGGAACGCUAUCUGGGCGCGGCGGCCGACGGCUGCGGCGGCGCCACAGUGCGCGACGCACUCUUCCCGGCUGAGGGCGGCGCGGCCGACUGCGAAAGCCCGCGCGAGUUCCGGGAGCGGGCCUUGCGCGCGCGGUGGGUCGAGGCGGACGCGCGGCUGCGCCAGGUUAUUCAAGGACACGGAAAAGCCAACACCAUGGUAGCAUUAAUGAACGUUUACCAAGAGGAAGAUGAAGCAUACCAGGAAUUGGUUACCGUGGCAACCAUGUUCUUCCAGUACUUAUUGCAGCCAUUUAGGGCUAUGCGAGAAGUUGCAACUUUAUGUAAGCUUGAUAUUUUGAAGUCUUUGGAUGAGGAUGACCUAGGUCCUAGAAGGGUAGUUGCCCUGGAGAAAGAAGCUGAAGAAUGGACCAGACGGGCUGAAGAAGCUGUCGUCUCUAUUCAGGAUAUCACAGUGAAUUAUUUUAAGGAGACAGUAAAAGCAUUAGCAGGAAUGCAGAAAGAAAUGGAACAGGAUGCGAAGAGAUUUGGUCAGGCUGCCUGGGCCACAGCAAUUCCCAGGUUGGAAAAACUUCAGCUAAUGCUAGCUCGAGAGACUCUGCAACUCAUGAGAGCGAAAGAGUUGUGUUUAAAUCACAAAAGAGCUGAAAUUCAGGGAAAGAUGGAAGAUCUUCCAGAACAAGAAAAAAAUACAAAUGUUGUAGAUGAAUUAGAAAUACAAUUUUAUGAAAUUCAAUUAGAACUAUAUGAAGUUAAAUUUGAGAUAUUAAAAAACGAAGAAAUACUGCUUACUACACAGUUGGACUCUCUUAAAAGACUUAUAAAAGAAAAACAAGAUGAAGUUGUCUAUUACGAUCCAUGUGAAAAUCCAGAGGAACUUAAAGUCAUUGACUGUGUGGUGGGGCUGCAGGAUGAUAAGAAUUUGGAAGUGAAAGAACUCAGAAGGCAGUGCCAGCAGCUGGAGUCUAAACGGGGCAGGAUCUGUGCCAAAAGAGCCUCUCUCCGGAGUAGAAAGGAUCAGUGCAAAGAAAAUCAUCGGUUCAGAUUGCAACAGGCUGAAGAAAGCAUAAGAUACUCUCGUCAGCAUCACAGUAUUCAGAUGAAAAGAGACAAGAUAAAAGAAGAGGAGCAAAAGAAAAAAGAAUGGAUCAACCAAGAACGUCAAAAAACACUCCAACGAUUGAGAUCAUUUAAAGAUAAACGCCUAGCUCAAUCUGUCCGAAACACCUCUGGCUCAGAACCUGUGGCUCCAAACCUGCCAAGUGAUCUUUCCCAGCAGAUGUGCUUGCCAGCUUCCCACGCGGUGUCAGUAAUUCACCCGUCCUCUAGGAAAACUAGAGGUGUUCCCCUAUCGGAAGCUGGUAAUGUGAAAAGCCCCAAGUGUCAAAACUGUCAUGGAAAUAUCCCUGUCCAGGUUUUUGUUCCAGUUGGUGAUCAAACACAUUCCAAAUCCAGUGAGGAAUUGUCACUGCCACCACCUCCUCCUCCUCCACCACCACCACCGCCGCCACCGCCGCCCCCACCCCCUCCUCUCCGUGCUCUGUCCUCAUCCUCUCAAGCUGCAACUCAUCAGAACUUAGGCUUCCGGGCUCCAGUGAAAGAUGACCAGCCACGUCCUCUAGUGUGCGAAUCACCUGCUGAGCGACCACGUGACUCCUUGGAAAGUUUUUCAUGUCCAGGAUCUAUGGAUGAAGUGUUGGCCUCCUUAAGGCAUGGCAGAGCUCCUCUCCGGAAGGUGGAAGUGCCGGCGGUGCGCCCUCCCCACGCCUCAAUCAAUGAGCACAUUCUGGCUGCCAUAAGGCAAGGGGUCAAACUGAAGAAAGUUCACCCUGAUCUUGGCCCAAACCCCAGCAGCAAACCAACCAGCAACAGACGCACCAGUGACCUUGAGAGGAGCAUCAAGGCUGCGCUCCAGAGAAUCAAGAGGGUGUCUGCUGACUCUGAGGAGGACAGUGAUGAGCAGGACCCUGGCCAGUGGGAUGGUUAGGCUCAAGUUUGACAAAGGCACCUGCCACAGUAGGCUUGAAUAAAGUGGGUGAGUCUUAGACCUAUCGAAAAGCAUACUAACAGGGUGCUGAUAGAUGGGCCACAUAACACCCCGGAAGAUCAGCAGGGCCUUGUGUAGGCUGCUGCAGCAUUUUUUUUUUUUUUCUUUUUUGAGAUGGAGUCUCACUCUGUCGCCCAGGCUGGGGUGCAGUGGCGCCAUCUCGGCUCACCGCAAGCUCCGCUUCCCAGGCUGGGGUGCAGUGGUGCGAUCUUGGCUCACUGCAAGCUCCGCCUCCUGGGUUCACGCCAUUCUCCUGCCUCAGCCUCCCGAGUAGCUGGGACUACAGGCGCCACCACCUUGCCCAACUAAUUUUUUGUAUUUUUUAGUAGAGACGAGGUUUCACCGUGUUAGCCAGGAUGGUCUCGAUCUUCUGACCUCGUGAUCCGCCUGCCUCAGACUCCCAAAGUGCUGGGAUUACAGGUGUGAGCCACCACGCCCAGCCUUUUUUUUUUCUUUCUUUUGAGACAGAAUCUCUCUGUCAUCCAGGCUAGAGUGCAGUGGCACGAUCUUGGCUUACUGCAACCUCCACCUCCCAGGUUCAAGCAAUUCUCUGUCUCAGCCUCCCGAGUAGCUGGGAUUACAGGCAUGCACCACCACGCCUGGCUAAUUUUUGUAUAUUUAAGUAGAGACAAGGUUUCGCUAUGUUGGCCAGGCUGGUCUUGAACUCCUGACCUCGUGAUCCACCUGCCUUGGCCACCCAAAGUGUUGGGAUUAUAGGCAUGAGCCACCGUGCCUGGCUGAUGCUGGAGCUUUUAUGUGACAUGGUGACUCUUAAAACUGGGGAGGGACGUAGAGAUGAGAGUUUCACACACCAGCCCAUAGGUGGGAUGUCAAGACCCAUCGGAAGUGUCGCUGGCCUAAGAGAAGAGCACUUAUUUCUCACCAUGGCUGAUCUAGAAUUGUUCCCUGAUUCUGAAAGAAGUUUACACUACACUGGUAAGCAGUACUAUUAGACUACUGACUGUGGCCUUCUGUGCAUAUGGAAUAAUGAUUUCUCAGAUUUGUAGGCUUGAAUGUGAAUGUUAUUUUAUCAGUAAUCAGAAUAAAUUGCUUAUAUUCAGGAGUUAUUUUAAAUAUUUAAAUGAAAUUUAUUUUAGGCACCAAGCACUACAUAAACUCAUAAUAACUAUUUGCAAUGCAUUAGCAUCACUCACGGGGUAAUGAAAACAUACCUUAGCUGCUGUAAAAGCAAAGUCUUCCGUGUCCGGGUGGGCUGAAAGUUUUUAAUAAAAUUUUAGCUAAACAUUUGUUUAAGUGAAUACUAAGGAUGGAGCAAUAGUGUUAUUUUCCUCAGGAACUGAAGUCUCAUGCUGAAGUAUUUUCUCCUUAAAAUUAAAUUUUUAAAAUCAGGGAAGGGGAAGGGACUGAUGCAAAGCAGUCCGUUCAUUUCUCAGACUGCGAGCAUCCCUACUAACCUCAUCACCCUCACUCUGGUGAUAUUACUCCUGGGUCUCCACAGAACAAAAGGAACGCACCUCGUUUACAAAGAAAGUCCUGAUUGAUAUAGAACAGAAAUCUUCCUACUUCAGUUUUUUUGUUUUUUUUUUUGAGACAGAGUCUUGCUCUGUCAACCAGGCUGGAGUGCGGUGGCACGAUCUCAGCUCACUGCAACCUCUGCCUCCUGGGUUCAAGUGAUUCUCCUGCCUCAGCCUCUCGAGUAGCUGGGACUACAGGCGUGUGCCACCACACCCAGCUAAUUUUUAUAUUUUUAGUAGAGAUGGGGUUUCACCAUGUUGGCAGGAUGGUCUCGAUCUCUUGACCUCGUGAUCCUCCCACCUUGGCCUCCCAAAUGCUGGGGGUUACAGGCGUGAGCCACCACACCUGGCCUUCCAGUGUCUUAACUAACUGGUACACAGCAGCCUGAGGGGCCUCAGUUGGCACAGCUGGGAGGGGCGUGAGUCCCUUUCAGCAGCUGCAGCCUGGGUCUCCCUCUGUGGCAUGGCCACUGCCAGGUUUCCCAGCCACUGCCAGGUUGCCCACGGGUCUGUCAUGUGUGCUACCUUUUCAGAAUGCAAAUCCAACUCCUGUGUAUGAAUGAAUGUGCCUCACUGUGCUGGCCCAGGCCUGAUGGGCCAAGCCCUGACUCUGCACUGGCCCCUGUACCUGCCGCUCCCACCCAGGUUCCCAGGGGUGUUCCAGUGGGGGACGCAACCUGCGGGCUACUCGCUGGGCAUCAGGUCCAGAUCCCAGAGACAGGUCCAGUGGCUGUGGCCCAGGCCUCCUUCCCCACCACAGACAGGCCAGGCUCAGCAUCAAACUUCCUAGGGAAAGAAUUUGGAAUUGAAAAAGUAGCAAAAUCACAACUUUGUGGGACUUUUCUUAUGCAUAUUUUGCAGUUUGGCAUUGUUUGUAAUUACGUAUUUAUAAUUUCAGUAUUUUGAGAUACCAGCGAGCUUAAUCAGGCUAAAAUAAUUCUCAGAAUUUGCUUUCUAAGGGCUGCCAAACACAAGAGGCCUUUGAAAAAAGGAUCCUUUUCAAAAGAACGUUCUCACAAUAAAAAUUCCUGGCCCAA